AUUCUCUGUCUACAAAAAAUUUUUAAAAAUAGCCAGGCAUGGUGGUGUGCACCUGUGGUCCCAGCUUUUUGGGAGAUUGAUGGUGCAGGAUUACUUUAGCCUGGCAGUUUGAGGCUACAGUGAGCCAUAAUUGUGCCACUUUACUCAAACUUGAAUGACAGAGUGAGAACCUGUCUCAAAAAAACUGUACAUUUCAGCCAUGUUUAGUAUAUUUGUAUUGUUAUGCAAAAGACUUCUAUAAAUUUUUCAUCUUGUGAAACUAAAACUCAAUACCCAUUAACAACUGCCCAUUUUAUCCUCUCUCCAGCCGUUGACAAACACCCUUGCACUUUCUAUGAGUGUGACUAAUUAAGAUAUCUCACAUAAGUGGAAUCAUAUAGUAUCCAUUUUGUUACUGGCUUACUUCAGUAAUGUGUUCUCAUUUUGCCCAAGAGUUUUGGCCAGAGCAGAACAUAAAAGAUUCUUUUGAAAAAGUGACACUGAGAAGAUAUGAAAAAUGUGGAAAUGAUAAUUUUCAGUUAAAAGGCUGUAAAAGUGUGGAUGAAUGUAAGUUGCACAAGGGAGGUUAUAAUGGACUUAACCAAUGUUUACCAACUAUGCAGAGCAAAAUGUUUCAAUGUGAUAAAUAUGUGAAAGUCUUUAAUAAAUUUUCACAUUCAGAUAGACAUAAGAUAAAACAUAUGGAAAAUAAACCUUUCAAAUGUAAAGAAUGUGGCAGAUCAUUUUGCAUGCUUUCACACCUAACUCGACAUGAAAGAAAUUAUACCAAGGUGAAUUUCUGCAAAUGUGAAGAAUGUGAAAAAGCUGUUAACCAAUCUUCAAAGCUUACUAAACAUAAAAGAAUUUAUACUUGUGAGAAACUCUACAAAUGUCAAGAAUGUGACAGAACUUUUAACCAAUUCUCAAACCUUACUGAAUAUAAAAAAGAUUAUGCUCGAGAGAAACCAUACAAAUGUGAAGAAUGUGGCAAAGCCUUUAACCAGUCCUCACACCUUACUACACAUAAGAUAAUUCAUACAGGAGAGAAACCCUACAAAUGUGAAGAAUGUGGCAAAGCCUUUAACCAGUUCUCAAAUCUUACUACACAUAAAAAAAUUCAUACUGGAGAGCAACCCUACAUAUGUGAAGAAUGUGGCAAGGCUUUUACCCAAUCCUCAACCCUUACUACACAUAAGAGAAUUCAUACUGGAGAAAAACCCUACAAAUGUGAAGAAUGUGGAAAAGCUUUUAACCGAUCCUCAAAACUUACUGAACAUAAAAACAUUCAUACUGGAGAGCAACCCUACAAAUGUGAGGAAUGCGGCAAAGCUUUUAACCGAUCCUCAAAUCUUACGGAACAUAGGAAAAUUCAUACCGAAGAGAAACCCUACAAAUGUAAAGAAUGUGGCAAAGCUUUUAAACACUCCUCAGCCCUUACUACACAUAAGAGAAUUCACACUGGAGAGAAACCCUACAAAUGUGAAGAAUGUGGCAAAGCUUUUAACCGAUCCUCAAAACUUACUGAACAUAAGAAACUUCAUACUGGAAAGAAACCCUACAAAUGUGAAGAAUGUGGCAAAGCUUUUAUCCAAUCCUCAAAACUUACUGAACAUAAGAAAAUUCAUUCUGGAGAGAUACCCUACAAGUGUGAAGAAUGUGGCAAAGCUUUUAAACACUCCUCAUCCCUUACUACACAUAAAAGAAUUCAUACUGGGGAGAAACCCUACAAAUGUGAAGAAUGUGGCAAAGCUUUUAGCCGAUCCUCAAAACUUACUGAACAUAAGAUAAUUCAUACUGGAGAGAAACCCUAUAAAUGUGAGAGAUGUGACAAAGCUUUUAACCAAUCUGCAAACCUUACUAAACAUAAAAAAAUACAUACUGGAGAGAAACUACAGAACUGGAAUGUGUGAUAAUGAUUUUGACAACACCUCAAAUUUUUCUAAAUAUAAAGGAAAUCAUACUGGUGAAAAAUUCUAGAAAUGUAAAGAAUGUGUCAAAGACUUUAAAUGGUUUUCACACUUCAUUGUAUGUAAGAUAAUUCAUACUGGAGAAAACUACAAGUGUGAAGAAUUUGGCAAUACUGUUAAUUAAGGCUCAAACCUUAUUGCACAGGAAAGCGUUUAUACUUAAGAAAAAUUGUACAAAUAUAAAGAGUGUAAAAUAGCCAUUAAUAUCUGUUGACAUCUUAAUAUCAGAAUGUUGGUACUUAAUAAAAGCAUUAUAAAUGCAAUUACUGUCUAAAGACUUUAAGAAAAUAUAAGCCUUUAAAGUGAAGAAGAGUAUUCGUUUUGAAGACAAAGAUUACAAACAUAAAGAGGGUUGUAGUACAUUUACU